AAGUGACGCGAGGCUCUGCGGAGACCAGGAGUCAGACUGUAGGACGACCUCGGGUCCCACGUGUCCCCGGUACUCGCCGGCCGGAGCCCCCGGCUUCCCGGGGCCGGGGGACCUUAGCGGCACCCACACACAGCCUACUUUCCAAGCGGAGCCAUGUCUGGUAACGGCAAUGCGGCUGCAACGGCGGUGAGUGCUGAGCCGGUGACCAGCACACUUUGGGCUUCUGGACGAGCCGUGCAGCGAUUGGCCCCAGGUUGCCAUCCUCAGUCGUCUAUUGGAAGAAAACAGCCCAAAGAUGAGAGUGAUUCGCGUGGGUACCCGCAAGAGCCAGCUUGCUCGCAUACAGACGGACAGUGUGGUGGCAACAUUGAAAGCCUCGUACCCUGGCCUGCAGUUUGAAAUCAUUGCUAUGUCCACCACAGGGGACAAGAUUCUUGAUACUGCACUCUCUAAGAUUGGAGAGAAAAGCCUGUUUACCAAGGAGCUUGAACAUGCCCUGGAGAAGAAUGAAGUGGACCUGGUUGUUCACUCCUUGAAGGACCUGCCCACUGUGCUUCCUCCUGGCUUCACCAUCGGAGCCAUCUGCAAGCGGGAAAACCCUCAUGAUGCUGUUGUCUUUCACCCAAAAUUUGUUGGGAAGACCCUAGAAACCCUGCCAGAGAAGAGUGUGGUGGGAACCAGCUCCCUGCGAAGAGCAGCCCAGCUGCAGAGAAAGUUCCCGCAUCUGGAGUUCAGGAGUAUUCGGGGAAACCUCAACACCCGGCUUCGGAAGCUGGACGAGCAGCAGGAGUUCAGUGCCAUCAUCCUGGCAACAGCUGGCCUGCAGCGCAUGGGCUGGCACAACCGGGUGGGGCAGAUCCUGCACCCUGAGGAAUGCAUGUAUGCUGUGGGCCAGGGGGCCUUGGGCGUGGAAGUGCGAGCCAAGGACCAGGACAUCUUGGAUCUGGUGGGUGUGCUGCACGAUCCCGAGACUCUGCUUCGCUGCAUCGCUGAAAGGGCCUUCCUGAGGCACCUGGAAGGAGGCUGCAGUGUGCCAGUAGCCGUGCAUACAGCUAUGAAGGAUGGGCAACUGUACCUGACUGGAGGAGUCUGGAGUCUAGACGGCUCAGAUAGCAUACAAGAGACCAUGCAGGCUACCAUCCAUGUCCCUGCCCAGCAUGAAGAUGGCCCUGAGGAUGACCCACAGUUGGUAGGCAUCACUGCUCGUAACAUUCCACGAGGGCCCCAGUUGGCUGCCCAGAACUUGGGCAUCAGCCUGGCCAACUUGUUGCUGAGCAAAGGAGCCAAAAACAUCCUGGAUGUUGCACGGCAGCUUAACGAUGCCCAUUAACUGGUUUGUGGGGCACAGAUGCCUGGGUUGCUGCUGUCCAGUGCCUACAUCCCGGGCCUCAGUGCCCCAUUCUCACUGCUAUCUGGGGAGUGAUUACCCCGGGAGACUGAACUGCAGGGUUCAAGCCUUCCAGGGAUUUGCCUCACCUUGGGGCCUUGAUGACUGCCUUGCCUCCUCAGUAUGUGGGGGCUUCAUCUCUUUAGAGAAGUCCAAGCAACAGCCUUUGAAUGUAACCAAUCCUACUAAUAAACCAGUUCUGAAGGUGU